ACAUACUUUUACGGUUACACAUUCCUUUACAAACAACCGUGUACAUUUCAGCCUCCUGCCCCACCAUUUCUUUUCUCCAGGAGGGAAGGCUGCAUGUCGAGAUGGUCGUAGAAUGUUGAGUAUCCUACUUUCCUACCUCGCUUUUAUUUGCGCGGGUUUAAAUGCGCCUUAACAGAACCCGUGCAAAGGCUUGCCUACUUGUCUGGCUGCACCGGAUGAGUAGAGCAUCUUCCUUGGUGGCAGGUGGGUGCGAGGAGGAGGGGGCUGGGCUUUUCUCCGGACGGUGUUUGCCCAGAAGACCAUCAUCCCUGGACUACGUUAGGAGGAAGUGGCACCGCUCCGAGGUAGGGGAAGAAGGGUUAUAAAGGGGGGAGUCCACCACACAUGGUCUUGAAGAAGCUUUUAUAAAAGGCAAAGGCAUCUUUGCCGGACGUUGUUGCAAAGGAGUAGAAACAAGCAGAGGAAAACAUCCCAAAGGGUAACCACUAGCGUUCCUGCUUCUUGCAACAUUCAUCCCAGGCUUCCAGCUCAGCCCGCCCCGGGCCAGGUGAUCGGCCGCCACAUCCCCUGCGACUGAAGCACCUGCUCCGCCAUGAACCUGCCAAGAGCUGAGCGCCCUCGCUCCACACCGCAGCGCAGCCUCCGGGACUCCGAUGGGGAAGACGGUAAAAUCGAUGUCCUGGGAGAGGAGGAAGAUGAAGACGAGGUGGAAGACGAGGAGGAGGAGGCGAGCCAGAAGUUCCUAGAGCAGUCGCUCCAGCCGGGGCUGCAGGUGGCCCGGUGGGGCGGGGUUGCGCUUCCCCGAGAGCACAUCGAGGGCGGCGGCCCGAGCGACCCCUCAGAGUUUGGCACCGAGUUCAGGGCACCGCCAAGGUCUGCGGCGGCCUCUGAAGAUGCCCGGCAGCCGGCAAAGCCCCCCUACUCGUACAUCGCGCUCAUCACCAUGGCCAUCCUGCAAAGCCCGCACAAGCGCCUCACGCUCAGCGGCAUCUGCGCCUUCAUUAGUGGCCGCUUCCCCUACUACCGCCGCAAGUUCCCCGCCUGGCAGAACAGCAUCCGCCACAACCUCUCGCUGAACGACUGCUUCGUCAAGAUCCCCCGCGAGCCGGGCCACCCAGGCAAGGGCACCUACUGGAGCCUGGACCCCGCCUCCCAGGACAUGUUCGACAAUGGCAGCUUUCUCCGGCGUAGGAAGCGUUUCAAGCGCCACCAACUGACCCCGGGAGCCCACCUGCCCCACCCCUUCCCUCUACCUGCUGCACACGCCGCCCUGCACAACCCCCGCCCAGGCCCUCUGCUUGGGGCCCCUGCCCUGCCGCAGCCAGUCCCGGGGGCCUACCCCAACACCGCCCCCGGGAGACGCCCUUACGCUCUGCUGCACCCGCAUCCUCCUCGCUACCUACUGCUCUCGGCCCCCGCCUAUGCCGGGGCACCGAAGAAAGCAGAAGGCGCGGACCUGGCGACCCCCGGCACCCUUCCCGUGCUGCAGCCCUCACUUGGUCCUCAGCCUUGGGAGGAGGGCAAGGGUCUGGCGUCGCCACCGGGAGGCGGAUGCAUCUCUUUCAGCAUUGAGAGUAUCAUGCAAGGGGUCAGGGGAGCGGGUACAGGGGCUGCGCAGAGUUUGUCCCCGACCGCGUGGAGCUACUGCCCCCUGCUCCAGCGACCGUCAAGCCUGUCGGACAAUUUUGCAGCAACAGCAGCAGCAUCAGGAGGAGGACUGCGCCAACGGCUGCGCUCCCACCAAGGGCGCGGUGCUGGGCGGGCACCUGUCGGCCGCGUCGGCGCUGCUGCGGUAUCAGGCGGUGGCAGAGGGCUCUAGGCUGACAUCGCUGGCUGCCCCUUUGGGCGGAGAGGGGACCUCACCAGUUUUUUUAGUAUCGCCCACGCCCAGUUCCCUGGCCAAGUCCGCAGGGCCCUCCUAGAGCCAGGUGGGAGUGGGGAGCGAUCCGCAGCUGCUCACUCCACCUUGCGCGGCCCAUACUGGGCGUGUGCAUCUGAAUCCUGCUGGAGAGCAAACACGAACUUCUGUUCCCUGCAAAAUGGUUAGAAAGAAACAGCUGGAUUACGUUCCUCUAAAAACCACCUGAACGUAACCUUCGCAGGGCGUCAAGUCAUCUUUUCUUGCCUUCGGCUGUGGCUUCUGUGGCUUUCCGGAUUUGCACAUUUCCUGGGGUACUAUGAACGUGAGUGGGGUAUUUUGUUCUGGCAUUAGAAGAAAAACAAGCAAGCAAACAAAAACACAGCCUCCGAUGCCAAACAUGUUCCCCCUUCUUCACUUCCUUGGAACUGGAAGUGUUAUUCCUAAGUCUAGUGCAAAAUGCUUCUACUCUCUGUGUCUUCCUGAUAGGGAUGUUUAAUGUAAGUAGGAUAUUAAUUUCAGAACAUUGAUUUCUUAUCUGUGUGUCUGACGUGCCAUCUUUAAUGUUAAAAUUAAGGUGUUAAAAUUAAGCCUAGUUAUAUAGACGAAAUAAAAUGCUAAGUCACUA